CAAAUGAGGCUGCUGCGGACGGCCUGAGGAUGGACCCCAAGCCCUGGACCUGCCGAGCGUGGCACUGAGGCAGCGGCUGACGCUACUGUGAGGGAAAGAAGGUUGUGAGCAGCCCCGCAGGACCCCUGGCCAGCCCUGGCCCCAGCCUCUGCCGGAGCCCUCUGUGGAGGCAGAGCCAGUGGAGCCCAGUGAGGCAGGGCUGCUUGGCAGCCACCGGCCUGCAACUCAGGAACCCCUCCAGAGGCCAUGGACAGGCUGCCCCGCUGACGGCCAGGGUGAAGCAUGUGAGGAGCCGCCCCGGAGCCAAGCAGGAGGGAAGAGGCUUUCAUAGAUUCUAUUCACAAAGAAUAACCACCAUUUUGCAAGGACCAUGAGGCCACUGUGCGUGACAUGCUGGUGGCUCGGACUGCUGGCUGCCAUGGGAGCUGUUGCAGGCCAGGAGGACGGUUUUGAGGGCACUGAGGAGGGCUCGCCAAGAGAGUUCAUUUACCUAAACAGGUACAAGCGGGCGGGCGAGUCCCAGGACAAGUGCACCUACACCUUCAUUGUGCCCCAGCAGCGGGUCACGGGUGCCAUCUGCGUCAACUCCAAGGAGCCUGAGGUGCUUCUGGAGAACCGAGUGCAUAAGCAGGAGCUAGAGCUGCUCAACAAUGAGCUGCUCAAGCAGAAGCGGCAGAUCGAGACGCUGCAGCAGCUGGUGGAGGUGGACGGCGGCAUUGUGAGCGAGGUGAAGCUGCUGCGCAAGGAGAGCCGCAACAUGAACUCGCGGGUCACGCAGCUCUACAUGCAGCUCCUGCACGAGAUCAUCCGCAAGCGGGACAACGCGUUGGAGCUCUCCCAGCUGGAGAACAGGAUCCUGAACCAGACAGCCGACAUGCUGCAGCUGGCCAGCAAGUACAAGGACCUGGAGCACAAGUACCAGCACCUGGCCACACUGGCCCACAACCAAUCAGAGAUCAUCGCGCAGCUUGAGGAGCACUGCCAGAGGGUGCCCUCGGCCAGGCCCGUCCCCCAGCCACCCCCCGCUGCCCCGCCCCGGGUCUACCAACCACCCACCUACAACCGCAUCAUCAACCAGAUCUCUACCAACGAGAUCCAGAGUGACCAGAACCUGAAGGUGCUGCCACCCCCUCUGCCCACUAUGCCCACUCUCACCAGCCUCCCAUCUUCCACCGACAAGCCGUCGGGACUCUAGGAAUCAUCAUUUCUGGAAGAAGCAGGCCAGAGGCUCCCCUGUCAGAAUGUCAGCACACAUCCAGUCCCCUGAAGCUCAGCCCCUUGUUCAUCCAGAACACCUGAGCCUUCCCAGUGGGCUGCCAUAUGAGAACUAUAUUCAUCUCUGCAUAAAUGAACCAUGUAUCUACUCCAAGUCAGUGCUUUCGGUACCAUUUCAUUGUAUAGGCAGGGAGAGAUUUUUACUGAAAAUAUCCUGCUUUACACUUAUUUCACACUUUUAAAAAUAACCACCAGUACUGGGAAUAGCAGCUUCUUGCUAAUUCCAAAGAGGGGCUGAACCUGAGUGCAGGAGGGUGGCCAGUGCAGAGGACAAGGGCAGCAUUGUUUUCAGAUGGGGUGGGUGAGGUGAGCUAAAUGCAAAGUGAGCAUCCACUGCAGCACCUCAAAGGAAAGACCUGGCCUGGGUGCAGGAUUGAGAGCAGGCGCUUUGGAGUAGGCUGGCUUGGAUUUAAAUCCGGUUUCCACCACUGAUUAGCUCUGGGACAUUAGGCAAGUCACUUUGUCCCCCUGAGGCUCGGUUUCCUCAUCUGUUAAUUGAGGAUAGAUUAAAAUAGUGCCUGUCACUUUAGGAAACGAAAUACUGCAAAAAACAUGUUUAGCACAAUGCUGGGUCCACGGUAAACUACAAGCCUCCUUUGAUCUAGGUCUUUUCAUCUUAAAACAAGGAGACUGAAAUAAACAGUCCCUUUUUUAGCUCUGGCGUUCCAUCUGUACACGUGUCUGCUUUAAAUCAGAAGCUCUGAAAGAGAGGGCAGGGUGUGUUAAUUUGUCUUGAUAGAAUACCGAGAGGGUAAAACGUGCCCUUGGGCACCAAACAAAGGCUCAGUUGAAUGUUGUUAUAACCCUGACUGGAGACAGGCUGGACUCAAUGGUUACUCAACAGAUCUCCUCUGGCCUAAGUGUCUCUGGUUUCUAACUCAAAACAUUUCAGGACAUUCCUGGGCUUGAACUAAGCUGGCAGAUACAUAGUAUAGGAAUAAGACCUGGGUUUGCAUCCAUGCUCUACCCCUUGGUUAGCUGUUCGCUCAUGAGAUAGUUAUUUAACUCUUCUGAGCCUCAAUUUUCUCCUCUGUAAAAUGGGGACAAGGGUCAUAACCUCACAGUGUUAUGCUGUGGAUACAAUACAAUCAAGCAUGAAACAUUAUGUCAUGUAGUAAAGCCAACAUUUGCUGAGCCCCUACUACAUGCUAGUCGCAGCACUAGACUUGGGGAAGUAGGUGACAAUUGUGGUCCCUGACCUCCAGAAACUCAGUCUGGGGUAGACGGCAGGUGCAUGAAUGCAUCUGGGAUCCGUCCAAUGCCCAUGAUUUCUAGUCCCUAACAUCAGCACAUCAGAUCUGACAAUGGAUUUCUCUGGGAGGGAGUAUCCGUCGAGGCCAAAAUUUCUAAAAUCAGGAAUGCAGUGAAAACUGGGCUGUCUGAUCACUGUGGUGAUACCCUGGUGUGCUAAGUGCCCUGGGGGACAGUAAGGUGGCAUGACUAAUUCUGCCUAGAGGGAAGGGAGAGAUUAGAUAGACGUGGCACUUCUUUGUUGCAUCUUGAAGGAUUUGUAAGAUUUUACCAGGCAGACCUGGGAGUUGGGAACCCAAGUGACUAGUGGGUCCCUGAUGGAGAUGAGUCUGUGCAAGGGCCCAGGGGCACAGUUCUAUUCCUGGCACCUCAAAUGGUUCAAUCUCCUGCUUCUUUGUGUUCACAACCCAGUGUGGGCUGUGUGUAUCCAAGUGUCCUGCACUCGCCCGUCUUUUGUCUCCCACUUAAGAAAGCACGCCGUCAUGGGAGGGAAUGGCAGUGAUUUCAUCACAGAGAUAACUGGAAUGCAUUAGAAUUUAUCCUUCUUUGUUACGCAAGGAUCCCCAAAUGUUGGUACUUGCUCAUUACCAGUAGAUUUCUUGUGACCCAUCUCACCACUGAGCUCCCACACAAGGCGCUGCCAGCUGGGAUUGAGUGCCUAGCUGUGGAAGAUGAAUGGGUAGACAGAGCCCAGGAAGAGAGCAGCUGGGGGAGGGUCCUGCCCUCUCCUGGUGUUGAGGACUAAACUGGGAGGAAAAAACAGAUGGUCUCUCUGCACGGAACAGUCAGGGCAUCCAAUGAGCAGAGAACAUUCUUAUCAGGUCUGUUCAGAGAGCUUGGGGCAGGUUCUUAUCCUGGAAGACAAAACACUCUUCUGUGCUCUUACCCAACAGAUCCUUUGUUCUUAGGGACAUCACUUAGCCAGAAAUACCUUUGCAAUUAAACACCUUUGCAUCCGAGCCUUGGCAGCUUCCAAACCUUUCACUCAGCAGCCUCAGAGCCAUGUGCUCUUUUCUUCGUCUGCCCACAGCAUGCCCUUCCCCAGGGGACUAAGGGAGCCAUGGCUGCUUAUCUGAAGCUGUACCACAAGCCUGUUCCCAGCCUUACUGAGACAGUAACAGGGUGGUCCCAGGCCAGGAUGGCCUACUGAGAGCCUGAGUGAGGAGGCACAGGCAGCUCCUGGCUUCCCUGGCUCCUCACCUGGGCUUUGUCCUGUGUCUCUCAGGUCUGGCCAGACCCAAAGGCAUUUUGAUUAGGAUGAUUCUGUGAUGAGGCCUGGGCCAAAUGGCCCUAUCUGUGGUCCUCUGCCCCACCUAUCCUGCUGCUGCUAUUAGAAGAGGAAGGCUCCAGGGGUCAUUCUCUAAGAGGCAAAGGAUAGAGCAGGCACCUGGGUUCUGGGAGGCCUGGUACUGUUUCUCAGGCCACCCAAGGCAGAGCCACACAUUUGCCAGCCCUCCUGCACAGUGCCCAUCCCAGAGACUGAUCAGGGAGGAAAGGACAGCGCCAACAGCAGCUGCCACAGACGGGCUUUGUCAGAAACUAAUCUUUAAAGACCAAAAGGAGUGAGCACUUUUAGCUGUUUUCUCUCCUGAGAAAGAGAAUACAACCAGUUCACUUUAUUUCUCAAUGAGUGAAGAAGAAGGGGCCAUAAAACCAUGAAAUACUGGAACUAUUAGGGGCCUCUCAGAUCCCCUAGCAUGGCCUUCCUGUAACAGAGCCUGUUGGUGGCAGAGCAGAGAUCGACCCUGGGACUUGUACCUUGCAGGAUAUUGAGGUUCAUAGAGGUCAAGUAACUUAGCCAAGGGUACACAGCUAGUAAGUGGCUUGGCCAAGGCUCAAACCAAAGUAUGUUUUAACUACUCUGGAUAUUGCACACUUCCACGGGAAGGCUGGAGGGGAACUGGUGUAAAAAUCACCCCGUGAAUGUCUGAUUUGGCCCCAGCUGCCACAGGGACCUGACCUUCUAUCUCUACUUCCUGACCUUCUAGCUCUACUUCCUGGUACCACGUUCCAAACAGUUCCUUAAAAUGAGCUCUGGGAACAAAGGUGGUAGAUUUGUUAUUAGAACAUGGUUCCAAUGACACAAAACACUGUCGCUACCAACCCACCAACAUCAUGCUCCCCCUCCCUAGGCCUAGCAGGAACCAGCCAAGCUCCCCAGUAGAAAGUACAACGUGCACCUGACUCCCAGCAAAUGGACCCAACUGAAGUCUAAUUUUUAAUUUUUAUCAAAUCUGGACAUAUCCUCUGGGGUUCCUUCUACUCAGCAUUUCAAUGUAUAGCUAAGUCUUUCAACAUAUAGCUAAGUGUGAAGUUCUGAUUUCUUUAAAUGUUAGCCCUGACUGUAUAAAUGUCAGUAGACAUGACCUUCCCUUGGGACCACAUGAGGAGGUCCCCACAUUGCUUCACUGACAAGAGUGCUAGCAGGAAGCCACCCCAUCUCACAACAGAUGGGCUAUUGGGCUAUGGCCAGGAUGGCAUGGACAACUUGAACAAGAGUGUUUUCCUAGAUGGAUUUUCCACCUGUAUUUUAUUCCACCCUAUAAGGUAGGAAAUACGUACACGAUUGUGGUUCCCCAGCACAAUGGUAUGUUUUAAAACAGAGAAAUAUAUGAUGUUGUAGCUCCCAUUCUUUCUGGAGGUCAAGCAAGCAACCAGGUGAAAAGGUGUCAACCCAUGUGUGGCUGGGUCAGCUUCAGUAGGCUGGGCAUCCAGGCCCAAGCACUGCAGAGAGGUGGAGAAGCACAGGGUGUGUGUGGUGAUGGUGGCGAGUGAGGGUGACUCUGCCCAUCCUGAGUCAGCCUUCAAGGUCACAGAGGCUGAGGGAAAAGCCCACACAGGUCUCCUGCCUCCAGAGCGUGUGCUGUUUCCACUGUACAAUACUUUCUUUUAUUCUAAAAGGUUUUGUUAAACAAAAUAAGAUUUCAAAUUCAGUACAAACUACAUAAUCCAGUGAUUUCUCAAAGAGCACUCUUUGCUAGCUUCUUCCUAAACAAAAUCUACUCUAGGAAGAUGGCCCACCUGGAUGAUGGUUCCAGGAGGGCCAGCUCCCUUAUUGCUUUGCUUUCUCUUCCUCCUCUUCUGGUACCUUGGGGAACUGAUCACAAAGAGCCUUUUGAGGGUGAUGGAAAGCUACCCCUCCAUUCCUCAGGCAGUUUUCCAAAGAUGACACUUGGCUAAAUGCUCAGGGUAUUUACAGUCAUAGGAGAUAAACUAUCAACUUGUUACUGUUAAAAAAAUCUUGAGAUCUGGGAUCUUGAUGCCUGAAAAUCCCAAGAUUGGUACUUGGCAAACUGAAAGAAAUCUAGAAAACCCUAGAGAUCAGGCAUCUGUGGCCAGCUAACUGGUCAUACAAAUGGAUUGUUGUGGUGAACUUGUAUAGUAUUAAUCCUGAGAUGCUGUCCCCCUCCACCCCCACCCCCACAAAAAAAAUAAAUAAAGUAGUAUUAAGUUAGCCUCAUACAAAUGCUGGCACCAUGCUCCUGGACUUCUCAGCCUCCAUAACUGUGAGCCAAAUAAACUUCCUUUCUUUAUAAAUUA